AUGGGUCCGGACGUGGGCGGCGGCGGCGGCGGGGCCGGGGCGCAGCGCUCCGCAGCGGGAGCCGCGGGCUGCUUGGUCGGCCUGCCCCGCCGGCCCCUCUUGUUGGAGCCCAGGCGGCGGGAGAAGGGAAAGCUGACGGGGAGGGCCGGGCGCAGUGGCGGCGGUGGGGAGCGCCGGGGCCGGGUUGGGAGGCCCGAGGGGCUGGGCGGGAGGGGCCCGGCCGGCGGAAGCGAGUGGAGGGAGAAGGCUCAACCGAAUUGCUGGGGCCCCACUCAAGAUCGCCUUCAACCGCCACCUUGUUUCUUCCCUCUACAGGAGCGCGGUCACGUGAGUGUCCCAGCUAGGAGCCUGACCACCUUAGCAAGAACUUACCUCUCCUUUGCAGUGGAAAAGAGGGAAUCCUGCCUAAAACCUACUUCACGGUGUUACAGAGAAGAUACAGAAAAUGAAAAUGAAAAUAAAAUUUGGUACUACAGCACAAAGGUCCAGCUUGCAGAAUUAAUUGACUGUCUAGACAAAGAUUAUUGGGAAGCAGAACUCUGCAAAAUUCUGGAAGAAAUGCAUGAAGAAAUCCGACACAUGGACAUAACUGAAGACCUGACCGAUAAGGCUCAGGGCAGUAACAAAUCCUUUCUGGUGACAGCUAAUGCCUAGGUUUUUGCAUUUUGGGGAGGAAGACCACAGAGGUGAUGUGCAGUUCUCGUCUUAUCAAGAGUGCAUGCCGUCGUCGUGACUUAUCACUGAUGAUGUUAACCUUGGUCCUC